AACCGCUCCCGCAUCCCUCGCCUGCACAGUGGGCAGUCUGGCGCCUGUGGCGUCGUGUUUGCUGAGGGCCCGGCUGCCGUUGACUGAGGCUGCGAUGGCGGCGGCAGGCCGGGGUCGGGAGCAGGACUCGGCGCGCUUCGUCUAUGUGACGCGCUUCGGCUCGCAUCAGUGCAGUGGCGUCCUGCAACUGGGCGGCCGUGGAGCUCAAGGCCUUUGGGGUCAGGGGCCUGGGGCAGGCUGUCGCCAGGAGAAGCCGAGGGAAGCAAUGGCGGUGGCGGGCGUUCAGGGUGGCAGCGAGCUGCCCCUCGGUUCCCAGCUCAGGGUCCCCACGACCCCUGGUGUGGAGGCUGCGGCCUCUGCCUCCUCCCAGCUGCGGGCAUCGAGAGUUCAGAGCGGCACCAGACAGUCGGCGCGUGCAGGUUUAAUCCAGAAGGAUGCAGCUAAAAAGUAUGAUUUUCCCAUACCAUUGAAUGAAGCUUCCAAAAUAAUGAAGAAAAAGAAAAAGGUUUUAGUAUGGAAUAGAGUAUACAAAGUCAUUUCAAGAAUGCUUGAAGAAAAUGAAAAAUAUAGACACAGGCUGAAAUGCCAAAGGUUAUCUAGUGAAAGCUCAAAUUACACAAGAUGAAUCUUCUUAUCUUCUGGGGCAUAAUUGACUGAUAGCCCAGCUGUGCUGUAUUGUGAAUUCUACUACAUUUGUAUGAAGCCAUUCUUCCCAACAAGUUGCACCCAAGCCAAUGAUUAAGCAUGGUAAGGAUUUUAAGGCAGGUGUGUUUCUCCAAGACAGGCCUCAAAGGUUCUCUGUUUGUCUUUCUGAAAAAUUCUUAGAACUGCACCAGAGAUAGCCUGAGACUCUCACAGUGGGCCCACUGGGUUUAGAAACCUACUCAAUAGCCAUCUCCCCAGGCCCUGGGUGUAUAAUUGGAAUUGAUAUACCUGGCAGUUGGAGUAACUCUUACGUUGGAUGCUUGUCUGGUGGAGUAAGAGUUAUCACAACGAGGAAGGACAAGUAGAAAUGCCUAAAACUGCCUCCUUUCUCCCAGCCAAGAUAAUAAUAAUAACAAUAGUAAUAAUAAUAAUGAGAUCACAUUCUGUGGAAUGGGAGGAGGGUGACAAAUUAUUGCUACCAUUAAAGACCCAAAGGACUGUAGACUACUACAAAGUUAAUUGAAUAGUAGCUCUGAACACAGCUGCUUUGCUAGACAGUUGCCAUUGUUAGAGCAGGAGCAUGGUAUAUAGCAAUUGAUGUGGCAGAUGCAUUCUUUUCCAUUUGAAUCAGAAAAGGUCACACAGUUGUAUUCACAUGGGGCAGACAGUAUUUACUUAAGGUUUUGCCUCAGGGCUAUGUUAACUCUCCUACCUUUUUUUUUUUUUUUUGAGACGGAGUCUCGCUCUGAUGCUGAGGCUGGAGUGCAGUGAUGCGAUCUUGGCUCACUGGAACCUCCGCCCCCUAGGUUCAAGUGAUUCUCCUGCCUCAGCCUCCUGAGUAGCUGGGACUACAGGUGUGUGCCACCACACUCGGCUAAUUUUUUUGUAUUUUUAGUAGAGACGGGGUUUCACUGUAUUAGCCAGGCUGGUCUCAAACUCUUGAGCUCAGGUGGUCGUCCCACCUUGGCCUCCCAAAGUGCUGGGAUUACAGGCAUGAGCUACCACGCCCAGUCCUCUCCUACCUUUCAUAAUAAUGUAGUCCAAAGAGAUCUGUAUUGCUUGUUCAUCCCACAGAAUUUCACACUGAUCAUUACAUUAAUAACUUUAUGCUGAUCAGCAGAACAAGCAACAGGUGGCUCGUAUACUGGAGGCCUUGGUAAAAGAUGUGUGUGCUCCCAAGGGUGGAAGAUAAAUGCUACAAAGAUUCAGGGACCUGCCUGGAUUUUCAGUGAAGAUUUUAGGAGUCCAACGUAGAAAGCUUGAGUGAUAUUUUUAGGGUUCCAGUGGCCAUGGGUAUGCUAGGAUAUCCCUUCCAGAGUGAAAAUCACUGCUCAAAUCUUGAUUCCCUCACCACAAAAACUGAAGCACAUGCAUGGUAGGCCUCUUUGUAUUCCUAGAAGUAAUAUAUUGUUCAUCUAGGAAUAUUGAUCCGGCCCAUAUAUUAGGUGACACAGAAGGUUGUUAACUUUGAAUGAGACACAGUGCAGGAAAGGGCUCUGCAGUAGUUCCAGGCUGUGGUGUAAGCAGUCCUGCUGCUGGAGUCAUAUGAUCUGGAAGACCUUAUGAUGUUAGAGAUGUCAGUAGUGAGAAAAGAUGUAGUAUGUUGCUUAUGGAAAGCCUAACACGGGCCCUGUAAUGGGAUUAUGGAUCAGGGUCAUGCUGUCCACAGCAUAGAAUUAAAUGCCUUUUGAAAAACAACUUCUGGGCCAGGAGUGGUGGCUCACGCCUGUAAUCCCAGCACUUUGGGAGGCUGAGGCCGGUGGAUCACGAGGUCAGGAGAUCGAGACCAUCUUGGCUAACACGGUGAAACCCCGUCUCUACUAAAAAUACAAAAAAUUAGCCGGGCUCGGUGGCGGGCGCCUGUAAGUCCCAGCUACUCGGGAGGCUGAGGCAGGAGAAUGGCAUGAACCCGGGAGGCGGAGCUUGCAGUGAGCCAAGAUCGCGCCACUGCACUCUAGCCUGGGUGACUCCAUCUCAAAAAAAAAAAAAAAAAAAGAAAGAAAAACAACUUCUGACAUGAUUCUGGAUUCUGGUGGAGACAGAUUUAUUGGUCUUGAGGCACCAAAUGACUGGAUCUGGGACUUCACUUUAUAAAUAGGAUUCUAUCAGACUUACCAAGUAAAAAAAAUUGAGUACUAGCAGUAGACUAUCAUAAAAUGGAAAUAGUGCAUCUGGACUGAAGACUGAGCAGGACCAGAGAGCACAGGCAAGUUACAUGAGCAGGUAGUCUAAUCCUCAUAUCAUCCACUUCGGUUGCACUAGCUAGAAAUGCCCGCUAGAAAGCCUCCAGUGUCCUAGAGGUUGCCGUGAGCCGAGAUUGCACCACUGUACUCCAGCCUGGGUGACAGAGCAAGACUCUAUCUUAAAAGAAAAAAAAUAAUCCUCCAGUGUCCUGGAGAGAUACUGGAAAUUAAGAAAACGGAAUGAUGGCCAGAUGAUUUUGCCAUCCUUCAUCAGUGGCCACCCAGGAACUCUCGUUUUUCUGUUUUCAGUUUCUUUCAUUUCUAUUUACUAUUUCCUUUCUUGUGUUUGCUUUGGUUUUAUUUUACUCCUCUUUUUUAUAUUCUUGAAACGAAUGCUUACAUUAUUGAGACUUUUCAUCUUUUCUACUAUAUGCAUUUGGUGUUAUAAGUUUUUCUGUCAACACCGCUUUAGCUGUAUCCUACAGAUUUUGAUAUAUUGUGUUUUCUCUUUUUUCCUCC